AGCGCCUGGCACCAUGAGGACGCCUGGGCCUCUGCCCGUGCUGCUGCUGCUCCUGGCGGGAGCCCCCGCCGCGCGGCCCACUCCCCCGACCUGCUACUCCCGCAUGCGGGCCCUGAGCCAGGAGAUCACCCGCGACUUCAACCUCCUGCAGGUCUCGGAGCCCUCGUUGGAAAAUAAAGUACAAAGAAGAAAAAAAAUCUUGCUUGUAAUUCUACCACCUAGAGGUAGCUGCUGCCGUAGCAUUGUGGAGGAUCAUAUUUCAGCUUUCUGUCUACAUAUAGGAGCCAUGUGUGAGAUACCUGCCCAGGCUGUACCUGGACAUACACAAUUACUGUGUGCUGGACAAGCUGCGGGACUUUGUGGCCUCGCCCCCGUGUUGGAAAGUGGCCCAGGUAGAUUCCUUGAAGGACAAAGCACGGAAGCUGUACACCAUCAUGAACUCGUUCUGCAGGAGAGAUUUGGUAUUCCUGUUGGAUGACUGCAAUGCCUUGGAAUACCCAAUCCCAGUGACUACGGUCCUGCCAGAUCGUCAGCGCUAAGGGAACUGAGACCAGAGAAAGAACCCAAGAGAACUACAGUUAUGUCAGCUACCCAGACUUAAUGGGCCAGAGCCAUGACCCUCACAGGUCUUGUGUUAGUUGUAUCUGAAACUGUUAUGUAUCUCUCUACCUUCUGGAAAACAGGGCUGGUAUUCCUACCCAGGAACCUCCUUUGAGCAUAGAGUUAGCAACCAUGCUUCUCAUUCCCUUGACUCAUGUCUUGCCAGGAUGGUUAGAUACACAGCAUGUUGAUUUGGUCACUAAAAAGAAGAAAAGGACUAACAAGCUUCACUUUUAUGAACAACUAUUUUGAGAACUUGCACAAUAGUAUGUUUUUAUUACUGGUUUAAUGGAGUAAUGGUACUUUUAUUCUUUCUUGAUAGAAACCUGCUUACAUUUAACCAAGCUUCUAUUAUGCCUUUUUCUAACACAGACUUUCUUCACUGUCUUUCAUUUAAAAAGAAAUUAAUGCUCUUAAGAUAUAUAUUUUACGUAGUGCUGACAGGACCCACUCUUUCAUUGAAAGGUGAUGAAAAUCAAAUAAAGAAUCUCUUCACAUGAGAAA